GUGAAGCAAGAGCGGUCGGCAGAGCGGGGAGGCGAACUGCAGCAGAGUUCUUGCUUUCCGGCAGGUGAUGGCGCCCCCCGCGGCCUAGAGGUCCAGCGCCCGCCGCGAGCAGCGGACAGUCCUCCUGUUGUGUCCGACCGAGAGUCCUGGUGACUUUGAACAUGCUGGUGCCGCUAGCCAAGCUGUCCUGCCUGGCAUAUCAGUGCUUUCAUGCCUUAAAAAUUAAGAAAAAUUAUCUACCUCUAUGUGCUACAAGAUGGUCUUCAACUUCUACUGUGCCUCGAAUUACUACCCAUUAUACUAUUUAUCCCCGGGAUAAGGACAAGAGAUGGGAAGGAGUGAACAUGGAAAGGUUUGCAGAAGAAGCAGAUGUUGUAAUAGUUGGUGCAGGCCCUGCAGGGCUCUCUGCAGCUGUUCGUCUAAAACAGUUGGCUGUGGCACAUGAAAAGGACAUCCGUGUGUGUCUAGUGGAGAAAGCUGCCCAGAUAGGAGCUCAUACUCUCUCAGGGGCUUGCCUUGAUCCAGGUGCUUUUAAAGAACUCUUCCCAGACUGGAAAGAGAAGGGGGCUCCACUUAACACUCCUGUAACAGAAGACAGAUUUGGAAUUUUAACAGAGAAAUACAGAAUUCCUGUGCCAAUUCUUCCAGGGCUUCCAAUGAAUAAUCAUGGCAAUUACAUUGUACGCUUGGGACAUUUAGUGAGCUGGAUGGGCGAACAAGCAGAAGCCCUUGGUGUUGAAGUAUACCCUGGUUAUGCAGCUGCUGAGGUCCUUUUUCAUGAUGAUGGUAGUGUAAAAGGAAUUGCCACUAACGAUGUAGGGAUACAAAAGGAUGGUGCACCAAAGGCAACAUUUGAGAGAGGACUGGAACUACAUGCUAAAGUCACAAUUUUUGCAGAAGGUUGCCAUGGACAUCUAGCCAAGCAACUAUAUAAGAAGUUUGAUUUGAGAGCAAAUUGUGAACCUCAAACCUACGGGAUUGGACUGAAGGAGUUAUGGGUUAUUGAUGAAAAGAACUGGAAACCUGGGAGAGUAGAUCACACUGUUGGUUGGCCCUUGGACAGACAUACCUAUGGAGGAUCUUUCCUCUAUCAUUUGAAUGAAGGUGAACCCCUAGUAGCUCUUGGUCUUGUGGUUGGUCUAGACUAUCAGAAUCCAUACCUGAGUCCAUUUAGAGAGUUCCAAAGGUGGAAACACCAUCCUAGCAUUCGGCCAACCUUGGAAGGUGGAAAAAGGAUUGCAUACGGAGCCAGAGCUCUCAAUGAAGGUGGCUUUCAGUCUAUACCAAAACUCACCUUUCCUGGUGGUUUACUAAUUGGUUGUAGUCCUGGUUUUAUGAAUGUUCCCAAGAUCAAAGGUACUCACACAGCAAUGAAAAGUGGAAUUUUAGCAGCAGAAUCUAUUUUUAAUCAACUAACUAGUGAAAAUCUCCAAUCAAAGACAAUAGGACUCCAUGUAACUGAAUAUGAGGACAAUUUGAAGAACUCAUGGGUAUGGAAAGAGCUAUAUUCUGUUAGAAAUAUAAGACCGUCCUGCCACGGAGUACUGGGUGUAUAUGGAGGGAUGAUUUACACUGGAAUCUUUUACUGGAUAUUGAGAGGAAUGGAGCCGUGGACUCUGAAACAUAAAGGUUCUGACUUUGAACGGCUCAAGCCAGCCAAGGAUUGCACACCUAUUGAGUAUCCAAAACCCGAUGGACAGAUCAGUUUUGACCUCUUGUCAUCUGUGGCUCUGAGUGGUACUAAUCAUGAACAUGACCAGCCGGCACACUUAACCUUAAGGGAUGACAGUAUACCUGUAAAUAGAAAUCUGUCGAUAUAUGAUGGGCCCGAGCAGCGAUUCUGUCCUGCAGGAGUUUAUGAAUUUGUACCUGUGGAACAAGGUGAUGGAUUUCGGUUACAGAUAAAUGCUCAGAACUGUGUACAUUGUAAAACAUGUGAUAUUAAAGAUCCAAGUCAGAAUAUUAACUGGGUGGUACCUGAAGGUGGAGGAGGACCUGCUUACAAUGGAAUGUAAACUGCAGCUAGCCAGUUUCUUUCAAGUAUGGCAAGCUAACGUUAAAAUGUUUAGAGAUUAACAGAUUUCAGAAUGUCUUUCUGCAUAUUACUGAACAGAAUAGUCACAAAAUGAUUAUCAAAUAAAAAUUUUAUACUAUAUGUAAGAUUGUCCCAUAAAGAAAUUACGGGUAUUGCUUUUAAAUAACCUUUAUAAGAAUGCAGCAUCUUCCUACCUCUUCAGUUCUUCAGAGAUUCAGUACCAAGAGCAAAAUUCACUACUGGACUUUACAUUUGACUUGCCAAAGUUAAGUAAUCAAAUAUAAAAAUGAAUAUAUAUUCUAGACUAAAGUUUUAUUGAAACACAGCCAUACCCAUUGGUUACACAUUGUCUAUGGCUAAUUUUGAAUUACAACUGUGCAGGUGAGUGGGUGUGACAUUACAUGGUCUACAAAGCCUAAAAACUUUAUGAUCUGGCCCUUGCAGAAGAAGUAUGCCCAUCCCUGAACAAGUUUGUGUGUGUGUGUGUGUGUGUGUGUGUGUGUGUGUGUGUAUUAUCUAUAAGUAUGAAAACCUAGCAUCAUCCACCAUGGAUACAUCAAAGAAUCGAAGGAAACAAUAUACAAACUUAAGCUCUCAUCUCUUUAUUCAAUAAGAUGUGUCUUUACAAGUUUAAAAAGACUGGACACCAUUAUUUUUUAUGAAUAAUGCACAUAACCAUUUUAAAAAACAUUUUACUUGGCCGGGCACGGUGGCUCACACCUGUAAUCCCAGCACUUUGGGAGGCCAAGGCGGGGUGGAUCACAAGGUCAGGAGUUCAAGACCAACGUGACGUGACCAAUAUGGUGAAACCCCAUCUCUACUAAAAAUACAAAAAUUAGCUGGGCGUGGUGGCACGUGCCUGUAAUCCCAGCUACUUGGGAAGCUGAGGCAGGAGAAUUGCUUGAACCCGGGAGGCAGAGGAUGCAGUGAGCCGAGAUUGCGCCACCGCACUCCAGCCUGGGUGACAGAGCAAGACUCCAUCUCAAAGAAACAAACAAAACCACUUUACUUACUGUAUUGUGACAUGUUUAUUAAGCAUGAACCCCUAUCAGUACUCCUAAACUGUAAACAGUAAG